CUCCUUGUUGCUUUGAAAUCUUAGAAGAGAGCCCACUAAUUCAAGGACUCUUACUGUGGGAGCAACUGCUGGUUCUAUCACAAUGAAACGGCUGGUUUGUGUGCUCUUGGUGUGCUCCUCUGCAGUGGCACAGUUGCAUAAAGAUCCUACCCUGGAUCACCACUGGCAUCUCUGGAAGAAAACCUAUGGCAAACAAUACAAGGAAAAGAAUGAAGAAGCAGUACGACGUCUCAUCUGGGAAAAGAAUCUAAAGUUUGUGAUGCUUCACAACCUGGAGCAUUCAAUGGGAAUGCACUCAUACGAUCUGGGCAUGAACCACCUGGGAGACAUGACCAGUGAAGAAGUGAUGUCUUUGAUGAGUUCCCUGAGAGUUCCCAGCCAGUGGCAGAGAAAUAUCACAUAUAAGUCAAACCCUAAUCGGAUAUUGCCUGAUUCUGUGGACUGGAGAGAGAAAGGGUGUGUUACUGAAGUGAAAUAUCAAGGUUCUUGUGGUGCUUGCUGGGCUUUCAGUGCUGUGGGGGCCCUGGAAGCACAGCUGAAGCUGAAAACAGGAAAGCUGGUGUCUCUCAGUGCCCAGAACCUGGUGGAUUGCUCAACUGAAAAAUAUGGAAACAAAGGCUGCAAUGGUGGCUUCAUGACAACGGCUUUCCAGUACAUCAUUGAUAACAAGGGCAUCGACUCAGACGCUUCCUAUCCCUACAAAGCCAUGGAUCAGAAAUGUCAAUAUGACUCAAAAUAUCGUGCUGCCACAUGUUCAAAGUACACUGAACUUCCUUAUGGCAGAGAAGAUGUCCUGAAAGAAGCUGUGGCCAAUAAAGGCCCAGUGUCUGUUGGUGUAGAUGCGCGUCAUCCUUCUUUCUUCCUCUACAGAAGUGGUGUCUACUAUGAACCAUCCUGUACUCAGAAUGUGAAUCAUGGUGUACUUGUGGUUGGCUAUGGUGAUCUUAAUGGGAAAGAAUACUGGCUUGUGAAAAACAGCUGGGGCCACAACUUUGGUGAAGAAGGAUAUAUUCGGAUGGCAAGAAAUAAAGGAAAUCAUUGUGGGAUUGCUAGCUUUCCCUCUUACCCAGAAAUCUAGAGGAUCUCUCCUUUUUAUAACAAAUCAAGAAAUAUGAAGCACUUUCUCUUAACUUAAUUUUUCCUGCUGUAUCCAGAAGAAAUAAUUGUGUCAUGAUUAAUGUGUAUUUACUGUACUAAUUAGAAAAUAUAGUUUGAGGCCGGGCACGGUGGCUCACGCCUGUAAUCCCAGUACUUGGGAGGCCAAGGCAGGCAUAUCAACUUGAGGCCAGGAGUUAAAGAGCAGCCUGGCUAACAUGGUGAAACCCCAUCUCUACUAAAAAUACAAAAAAUUAGCCGAGCACGGUGGUGCAUGCCUGUAAUCCCAGCUACUUGGGAGGCUGAGGCACGAGAUUCCUUGAACCCAAGAGGUUGAGGCUAUGUUGAGCUGAGAUCACACCACUGUACUCCAGCCUGGAUGACAGAGUGGAGACUCUGUUUCAAAAAAACAGAAAAGAAAAUAUAGUUUGAUUCUUCAUUUUUUUAAAUUUGCAAAUCUCAGGAUAAAGUUUGCUAAGUAAAUUAGUAAUGUACUAUAGAUAUAACUGUACAAAAAUUGUUCAACCUAAAACAAUCUGUAAUUGCUUAUUGUUUUAUUGUAUACUCUUUGUCUUUUUAAGACCCCUAAUAGCCUUUUGUAACUUGAUGGCUUAAAAAUACUUAAUAAAUCUGCCAUUUCAAAUUUCUAUCAUUGCCACAUACCAUUCUUAUUCCUAGGCAACUAUUAAUAAUCUAUCCUGAGAAUAUUAAUUGUGGUAUUCUGGUGAUGGGGUUUAGCAACUUUGAUGGAAGAAAAUAUUAGGCUAUAAAUGUCCUAAGGACUCAGAUUGUAUCUUUGUACAGAAGAGGAUUCAAAACGCCACGUGUAGUGGCUCAUGCCUGUAAUCCCAACACUUUGGGAGGCUGAAGUAGGAGGAUCGUCUUGAGCCCAGGAGUUCAAGACCAGCCUGGACAACAUAGUGAGACCUUGUCUCCACAAAAAUAAAAAAGAAACUAUCCAGGAGUGGUGGUGUGUGCCUGUGGUCCCUGCUAUGCAGAUGUCUAAGACAGGAGGAUCACAAGAGCCCAGGAGGUUGAGAAUGCAGUGAGCUUGUAAUUGCACCACUGCACUCCAGCCUGGGUGACAGAGCAAGACCCUGUCUUAAAAAAAGAGGAUUCAACACAUAUUUUUAUAUUAUGUUAAAGUAAAGAAAUGCAUAAAAGACAAGCACUUUGGAAGAAUUAUUUUAAUGAUCAACAAUUUAAUGUAUUAGUCCAAAUUAUUUUUACGUAGUCAUCAACAAUUUGACCAGGGCCUUUAUUUGGCAAAUAACUGAGCCAACCAGAAUAAAAUAACCAAUACUCCACUGCUCAUAUUUUUAUCUAAUUCAGAUGGAUCUUCCUUACAACUGCUCUAGAUUAGUAGAUGCAUCUAAGCAGGCAGCAGGAACUUUAAAUUUUUUAAGUUCAUGUCUAUGACAUGAACAAUGUGUGGGAUAAUGUCAUUAAUAUAUCCUAAAUUAACCUAAACGUAUUUCACUAACUCUGGCUCCUUCUCCAUAAAGCACAUUUUAAGGAACAAGAAUUGCUAAAUAUAAAAACAUAAAUAAUACCAUAAUACAUGGCUAUCAUCAAAAGUGUAUAGAAUAUUAUAGUUUAAAAGUAUUUAGUUGAUUACUUUUCAGUUUUGUUUUGUUUUUUGAGACGGAGUCUCACUCUGUUGCCCAGGCUGGAGUGCAGUGGCACCAUCUCAGUUCACUGCAACUUCUGCCUCCCGAGUUCAAGCGAUUCUCCUGCCUCAGCCUCCCGAGUAGCUGGAAUUAUAGGCGUGCACCACCACGCCCAGCUAAUUUUUGUAUUUUUAGUAAAGACAGGGUUUUGCCACAUUAGCCAGGCUGGUCUCAAACUCCUGACCUCAGGUGAUCCACCCACCCCAGCCUCCCAAAGUGCUAAGAUUACAGGCGUGAGCCACUGAGCCCAGCCUACUUUUCAGUUUUUAACAUAAUUUUUGUUUUAUCCACAACUUUUCAAGUAUUGAAAGUAGAAUAAAAACAUGGGUUCUUAGUCUUUAGCUAUCUGUUAAAGCCUAUGAAUGCCUUCUUAAAAUCAUGUUUUUAAAUGCAUAAAAUAUAUAGGAUUACAAAGGAAUCUAAUUAUAUCGAAAUACAGUUAUUAAAAUGUUAAAAGAUAAGUUUGUUAUAUAUUAAUAUGCAUGCUUCUUUAUAAAUGCAUUAAAUAAGAGUUAAUAGCUAUCCUAAAUUUGAAAUAGUGAUAAGCAUAAUGAAAAUAGAUGCAAAAAACUAAUGUGAUAUGAAAAUAUCUGGGUUUUUCUUUUGAUGAUGAAGUAUUGCUAAUAUUACCGUGGUUUAUGAACUAUGUUCAGAAUUGAAGAAAAUCCUAACUUUCAGUUAGAGGUUAGUGACGGGGUUCAGGACACCCUACACAAAAUACAGCACUUUGACAUAUUGAAUAUUUUAAGCUGAAGGCAUUUGAGGAAAUUGCAGAAGCAGGAAGGUGACUCUGACCUUCUGCCUGCUGUUCUCCCCAGAAGCAGCCAUAAAACCUGGGAAGGAUUUUCUGACCUUCCCCUGAAGUAGAUCAUAAGACUGUCAUGUAAGAGGUGCUCUCCUGGCACCCAGAGAAAAGGAGCAUCCUUACCUCCAAAAGCACAGGGACACAAAGAGGAAUCUAAACAAACAGGCCUCUCAGUUUCCCCCAGUUUAUUACAUUUAGCUUGUUCACACUUUGCCCUAUGACAUUUCUACAUCACUGGCUGCUCUUCAUCAAACCUACUAUAAAAAACAUUCAAGUUCAACUGUUUCUUUGGGCCUUUAUUUCCUUAUGGAGCCCCUCGUGUCGUGUAAAACUUAUAUUAAAUAAAUGUGCAUGCUUUUCUCUUGC